ACUCUGCUCCCCUGGGUUAGGAGCGGGACUUUGCCUCCCGCCUGGGGUCUGCAUUUCAGCUCCAGCUUCAGUGACUCAUCCCAGCAGGCUGACCCCCUCCUGAGGCUGGACCAGCUGCCUCUCCGUCUAGGUGAGGGCCAGGCAAGUUUCUCGUCUUCUGAUGCUUACUGUUUGGGGGACUCGCGGGGAGGGGGUCUUCCAGCCUGUGUCUGUCUGCCUUUGCUUCCUCCCUCUGGCUCUCUCCAUUGGAGACAGAAAGUUAGAUUUAAAAAACGCAACAGAGAAUAUAAAAUCUAUGCUCAGACCCCAGAUAAACAAAACUCUGGGGCCAUAUUCUUAAUUUACCGGGUACCUUCACAUGUCCGAAUGCGGCGUUUAUGGAGCUAGGAAUGUUUUAUUUGUUUCGUGUAUUUCCCUCCUCUCCCCCAUUUUCCUCCGGUGUAAUUCUUAGAGGUGGGGACAGGAGAGCCAGAGGGCUUAGCUGGGAUCCUUUGCCAGAGUGGCUUCUUCAUUCUCUGCGAGGUAGCAGAUGUUUUACUGUAGCCUGAGUUGGGAUCUUGGAACAACCCUCUCCAGCCCAGGACAUGCCAGCGCUUAAGGUGCACUGGCUGAGCGCCAUCAAUUAUACACAUUAAUGCAAUUAGUCAAGAUACAGAAGCUUGUAUUCCAAAUGAAAAUUUCCUACAUCUGAGGCAUCUGUGUAAAAGUGUUUUCUGCAUUCUCUCCCAGCGGAUCUGAUUCCUGUUCUGAAGAAUUGAAGUUGAGCAUCGUUAGUUAAAUUCAGCUGCUGCCUGACUGUAUACCACAGCAAAGGCUUUGGAAACAUUUUUCAGUUAAAACAAUAAUGACUUUCUUGGAGUGUAAUCCCAGUGGAGGCUGUUCUACGUAUAGCCUGAAAGAAUACUUAACUACCAUACGCAAUUCUGCAGAGACCUUGUAAAAAUCACACUUUACACCAAACAACUGAGUGAUUCUGAAUUGGUUGGGGGAAUCUUAGUUGUAGAUAUCAAUUCACCUUCUUGAAGAUUCAACCACUGCUACUCAGAGCUGCUGCUGAAAUACCAUGUCUAAGAACUCAGAGUUCAUCAAUCUGUCAUUUUUAUUAGAUCAUGAGAAGGAAAUGAUCCUGGGCGUCCUAAAGAGAGAUGAAUAUUUGAAAAAAGUGGAGGACAAGAGAAUAAGGAAGCUGAAAAAUGAACUCUUAGAAGCAAAACGUAGAAGUGGGAAAACUCAACAAGAGGCCAGCAGAGUUUGUGUUCACUGUCACAGAAACCUGGGCCUAAUCUUUGACCGGGGAGACCCUUGUCAGGCUUGCUCACUGAGGGUAUGCAGGGAGUGUCGAGUUGCAGGCCCCAAUGGCAGCUGGAAGUGCACUGUCUGUGACAAAAUCGCGCAGCUAAGGAUUAUAACUGGUGAGUGGUUUUUUGAAGAAAAGGCAAAACGUUUCAAGCAAGUCAAUGUUCUCGGCACUGAUGUUGUCCGACAGUCCAUUUUAAGAAGAAGUCCAGGAGCUGAAGAAGUACAGAGCCAAGAGCAAACCCGCCAGGAUGCAGAAAAGUCAGACACUUCACCUGUUGCUGGGAAGAAGGCCAGCCAUGAUGGGCCCAAGAGAAAGGGAUUUCUUCUUAGCAAGUUCAGAUCGGCAACCAGAGGAGAAAUCAUAACUCCCAAAACUGACACUGGGCGGAGCUAUAGCUUGGACUUAGACGGUCAACAUUUUCGGAGUUUAAAAUCACCUCCUGGUUCAGACAGGGGAAGCACUGGCUCAUCAGAUCUCAAUGACCAGGAACCUGGUCCUAGGACCCCGAAGAGCAGUCGGAGCAAUGGUGUGACCCCAGGCACUCAGAGUUCACCAGCCCCAAGCACACGAACUGUGACCUCAGUCAUCAGUAGAGAGUAUGGUUUUGAAAAUUCCAUGGAUUUGGCUGCUAUUGAAGGUACCUCUCAGGAGCUCACAAAGAGUCACCGCAGAAACACUUCUGGCACACCUUCCAUAGCAGUGUCUGGAACCUCUCUCUCCUCAGAUCAGAGUCGAUCUGAGUUAGAUUUGAGUGAGUCAUUUACAGAAGACUCAGAGGAUACUGUAAGCAUAAGAAGCAAGUCUGUCCCUGGGGCUUUAGACAAGGACUCCUUGGAAGAGACUGAAGAAAGCAUUGAUGCCUUAGUGUCCUCGCAGUUAUCUACAAACACUCACCGUCUGGCAAGUGGCCUAUCAACUACCAGCCUUAACAGCAUGAUGAGCGUUUACAGUGAAACGGGAGACUAUGGCAACGUGAAAGUCAGUGGUGAAAUCCUUCUCCAUAUCAGCUACUGCUACAAAACUGGUGGGCUGUACAUUUUUGUCAAGAAUUGCAGAAAUCUGGCCAUAGGAGAUGAAAAGAAACAGAGGACAGAUGCUUAUGUCAAGUCAUAUCUUCUUCCUGACAAGUCCCGGAACAACAAGCGUAAGACCAAAAUCAGAACAGGCACCAAUCCAGAAUUCAAUGAAACACUAAAGUACACUAUCAGCCAUACCCAGCUGGAAACAAGAACUCUGCAGCUCUCAGUCUGGCACUAUGAUCGAUUUGGACGUAAUAGCUUCCUCGGGGAAGUAGAGAUUCCUUUUGACUCAUGGAACUUUGAAAAUCCAACUGAUGAGUGGUUUGUGCUUCAACCCAAGGUGGAGUUUGCUCCUGAUAUUGGCCUUCAAUACAAAGGAGAGCUGACAGUUGUUUUACGUUACAUUCCCCCAGAAGAGAACCUGAUGCUUCCACCAGAACAACUCCAAGGAAAUAAGACUUUUAAAAAGGGAAAGAAGAAGGAGUCACCUGUAAUCUCUGGAGGAAUACUAGAAGUGUUCAUCAAAGAGGCAAAGAAUUUGACAGCAGUGAAGUCAGGAGGCACUUCUGAUAGCUUUGUGAAGGGCUACCUGCUCCCUGAUGAUAGCAAAGCCACCAAGCACAAAACUCUGGUAAUAAAAAAGAGUGUUAACCCUCAGUGGAAUCAUACAUUCAUGUUCAGUGGCAUCCAUCCCCAGGAUAUAAAGAAUGUUUGCCUAGAACUUACUAUCUGGGACAAGGAGGCCUUUUCCAGCAACAUCUUUCUGGGAGGAGUUCGUUUGAAUUCUGGAAGUGGUGUGAGCCAUGGGAAGAACGUGGAUUGGAUGGACUCUCAGGGGGAAGAGCAGCGCCUUUGGCAGAAGAUGGCCAACAACCCUGGAACUCCCUUUGAGGGUGUACUCAUGCUUCGUUCCAGCAUGGGAAAAUGUAGGCUCUAAAGGGACCAGUUCUCCAAGAAUGAGGCCACCAGGACCUAUCUGGCUGUCUUUUCCUACCAUUAGCAAACUGAGACCUGGGAUUCUGCUUCCCUGCCAUUUCUCACCUGACAGUGUUGGGACAUGAGGGGAGAGAUGUCAGUAGUAUGAACAUUUAGGGUCUUGCUGAGUGCCUAAAAAACAUAUAUUUCCAUCCAAUCAAGGCCUUCUUGAUUGGAUGAUAGAAAGUGUACUACUUGUCCUGUCAACAAGCAAAUUGUGCAAAGGCUUAUAGGGUUUAUGCCAUAAAAGAAAUGGCACAAGCCUCCAUUUGCUAAUUAUAAGUUACUUUAGAUUUCCUCAAAUCCUUUGAAGAGAAAGAGGACCACUGAGAAGGUAGAUCACUUGAAAAGUCAGAAGAAAGGAUACUGGCCAACUUUUACUCACCCUAGGAAUCCACAUGAUCUCAAGAAGGCAUGGUGGAGAUGGUUGCUUGAGCAAGGGGAUUGUCCUGUUAUUGCAGCAAACUUGUGGAUUAACCAAGUAGUAUUUCAAGAUGGAUUGACAGGGCUUUCUAUGAUUACUAUAGAAUUUAUCAUCUAAAUCAGUUUACUUUUUAGAACAAAGAGAGCUAAAUAACUACAUCAGAACGAUUGAUGUUGAUUAGAAUUGACCUGGGAAAAUUGGGAUGUAGGGUCACCCUACUGAUGACCUAAGAGAGCUCUGUUUUAAACAUUUAUUUUAUAAAAUGUUCUAAGCCAUUAACUAAAAGGAAAUGAGAUAUAAUGGUCAAUUGAUAUACCUUUUCACAUUGUGUUCACUGACGAGACUAGUUUAAUGAAAAAGGAGGUACUCUACCUGCUAUUUUACUUCUGUUCCUCUUCUGCCCUGUUAUGGGAGAGAAUCAAAGACUCCAUCUGCUCUCUUCCCCCUUGUUUUCUCCUUCACUGAGUUUUUCUUAUCUCCUUUUGCAGUGGUUAACUAUUGUCACAAUAAUGCUGAAUGAAAAAACACACCAAAUGUCAGUGGCUUAAAAUGACCAUCCUUUUUCUCACAGUUAUGAAGAUUGGCUAUGGCACCUCUGCUUCCUGCUAUAGGCCUGAGGUUCUAGGGCUUCUUAUGCCUCAUCCUCUUUAAGCCAAAGGGAUAGCCAGAGCAUCUUGAUGGCAGAAGUGCAAUAAGAUGAGCCCCACUGCUCGGGUACAUUUUCAGCCCCUGGUUGUGUCAUGUCUACUGAUAUCUCAUUGGUCAAAGGAAGUCAGAGGGCCAAGAUGAAGAGGCAGGGAAAUAUGCACUGCCCACAGUGAAGCCAUGACAAGAGUGAGGAUGCAGGAAGGCAUGAAGAAUUGGGGCCAACAGUUCAAUCUACCAUACCUUCUCUCACCUGGAAUUCCAGAUGCUUGAGCUACGAAACUUAGAUGCAAAGAAAGUUAAAGCUAGAAGGAACCUCAGGCCCAGUUGCUCAUUUUGCAGAUUCCAAAUGUGAAUUUCAGAGAGCUGAGAUAACUUGCCCAAGGCCAUAUAGAGGCUGUGACUAAAUCUGGACUUAAAUCCAGACUAUCAAUCUUAGGCCAGUGUUCUUUUUUCAAUAUAGUCCUUGGCAUAAUGCUAUGCUUAUUAGGUAGAUAAAAGGGCUUAUGUCAAGAAAUUUGGAGCAGAGUCUGAUUACUUGAGCAUGAACAUACCCGACCAAGGUAUGUUCUGGAGUCAUAUUCUAGCCUCUGAGCUCAUUUUUUCAUGCGAGUUCAUAUAAAAUCCUCGAAAGUUUAGAAACUAGGUUUUAGUAGUAACGGAGCUAGAAUCAUCUUCGGGCUUAUUCCUGCUAGUUGUUCCAUAUUUCUAGAUUUCAUCUUGAAUUUUGAAAACUGAUUUAAGAAUAUAUUUAGUAUUAUUAUUAGUAAGGGAAUACGCAAUCCAGUUUCAAUUUUAUUCAGAAGUAGGUCACCUAAUUCUAGAAAAUGGUUAUUAGUCUAGUGUCGCUUAGCAAGGUACUUAAAAGAAAAUCUGCACAUAUCCUUGUGCUGCCCUUCUUAAAAACAGAAAACAAAAAGUGUAAGAUCAUCAUUGCUUCCCACAUAGGAAAAAUAAAAUGUCUUCAGACUUGAUGUGACUCA